CGCCGCCCGCCGCCGCCCAGGGCCCGAGCCCGCGCGGCGCACACUCAGCCCGGCGGCGCCGCGUAGCCGAGGGAGCCCGCCUGCUGCGAGCCAGGCGCGGGGCGUCAAGGUCACCGGCCCGACGGGGCGCACGCGCGGCCAUGGAGGCCAAGGUCCGCCCGAGCCGGCGCUCGCGCGCGCAGCGGGACCGUGGCCGGCGCCGGGAGGCCGCCCGCGACGCCCGCGCCCAGAGUCCGUCGUCGGGCGACGAGCCCGAGCCCAGCCCCGGCAAGGAGAACGCGGGCCUCCGCGGCGCGCCCCCCCGAGGCGCCGCCCCCGCGCCCCGCACCGCGCGUCCCCCGCGCCGCCGCCGCCGCGAGUCCAGCUCGCAGGAGGAGGAGGUCAUCGACGGCUUCGCCAUCGCCAGCUUCAGCACCCUGGAGGCCCUGGAGAAGGAUAUGGCCCUGAAGCCACAUGAGCGGAAGGAGAAGUGGGAGCGUCGUCUCAUCAAGAAGCCCCGGGAGUCGGAAACCUGCCCCCCUGCGGAGCCCAGUGAGAACAGGCGGCCCCUGGAGGCAGGCAGCCCCGGGCAGGACCUCGAACCCGCCUGCGAUGGGGCGAGAAAGGUCCCACUGCAGCCCUCCAAGCAGGUGUGCUCCCCAGAAGGGGGGCCGCUCCCAGCCAGCCACUGGGACCAGAACGGCCCGGCCCAGCGCCAGCAACAGCUCCAGCCCAGCCAGUCCAGCCAGCCCCAGGGGUCCCUCCCAGCCCCGUCGGCACUCCCGGACCCUGGGCAGCCCUGCCAGCCCUCCCAGCGGCCACUCCUGGGUCAGCGCAGCUGGCCCCAGCGGUCACUUCUGGGCCUGAAACAGCCCUGCCAGCCCCGGCGGUCACUUCUGGGCCCCGGUCAGCCCUGCCGGCCCCAGCGGCUCCUUCCAUCCCCAGAUCAGCUCUGCCAGCCCCAGCGGUCACGCCCGGCCCAGCCCUGCCGGCCGCAUUGGGCACUCCCAGGCCCCAGGCAGUGCUGCAGGCGCCUGCGGUCCCUGCUGACCCCGUGUCACCACUGCCGGCGCCUGCGGUCCCUCCUGGCCCCACGGUCCCUCCUGGUCCCCUGCCUCUACUGCCGGCGCCUGCGGUUCCUCCUGGCCCCAAGGCACCGCUGCAGGCGCCUGCGGUCCCUGCUGACCCUGUGGCACCGCUGCCGACCCCUGCGGCCGUGGGCCAGCCCGUGUCACUGUGGCCAGCCCGGUAGGGCAUCCUCAGGACAGCGCAGCCGGCCCCUGUGGUCGCUGCUAGCCCAGUGCCAGCGGUACCAGCCCCCGCGGCCACUCCUCACCCUCCGACCACGCCGACGGCCCGCCAGCUUCCUCCCAGGACAGUGCUGCUGCCCCCGGCGGGCCUUCCUAGCCCCGUGUCAGUACGGCCAGCCCCGAAGGUCCCUGCUGGGCCAGCCCAGCCGCCCCCGGCGGUCGCUGCUGCGCCCCAGGCAGCCCCAGCGGUUAGUGGAAGCCCCAGAGCAGCCCGGCCCACUCACGCCUUCACUCCUGGGCCCGGGACGGCCGAGGCAGCAGAAGCAGCCGCUCAUGGGCCCGGAGCAGCCCUGCCCACCCAAGCGGCCGCUCAUGGGCCCAGAGCAGCCCUGCCAGCCCCUGCGGCCGCUCAUGGGCCCCAACAAGCCCUGCAAACCCCAGCCGUUGCUCCCCAUUCCCGAUCGCCCUUCACUCCUGGGGCAGCCGGGCCCACCCUGCCGGCCUCUCCUGGGGCUCCUGUGCCAGCCGCGGCGGUCCCUAUUGGAUCUGGUGCCGGCCCGUCAGCCCCGGCUCUCGCUCCUGGCCCUGGGCCAUCCCUGCCGGCCCCUGCGGUCCCGGUGGACCCGAUCCUGUGCCCCCGGGAUGGCCCGUCAGGCCCCAUCUGUGAGCCCUGGAGCCUGAUGCCUGCAGGCACCUCCCCAUAUGGGUUUUCCAGCCCACUCCAGUGUGAUCUGCACCCUGGCAGGGCCCCAAGGGCCAAGGCCGCAUUGCCCUUCGGGCUGGAGAUGCUUUGCCGGACUAGCCUGAGGCCUUGUCUAGACAGGGCUGAGCUGUUUGUCGUUGGAAAUUGAGGCUCGGCCAGAGGCGGGAGCCCCUACAGUGCCACGAUCAGGCUGAGGCUCACCACACCAGGAAGAGAGAUGAACCCGCGUCUGCCUGCCGCCCCGCCAUGCUCCCUCUCCCCCCACUGGCGUCACAGUGCCCCCACCCGCGUUGCUGCCUGUGGUGUGCGUGCCCUGGGAGGGGAACACAGCCCCUGAGGGCGGGGACCUUGCUGGGGGCCCCUCAGCGUCUUUCUGUGCCUCUGAAUUGCCAAUACUGUCCUUGCAUCUCUGAGUCUACGUGCACGCUUGCCCCUGGCGUGCCACCUGUGCGGAGCGCGUGAGCCUGGUGUGUGCGUGCUGUGUGUGCAUGUGUGCGAGAGGGUGUGAGAGUGAGUGGCGUGCUGGGCAUGAAGGAUCUGUGGGGUGCUGCAGUUCCUGCAGAGUGGCCCAGUGGCGAAUGGUGAAGGUGUGGGUUUCAGUCCAGGCCCUCCCCCUGGUAGUCAGGAGGUGCUGGUGUCCACCUCCAGGGCCCCCAAGCUACAGGGGGCACAUGGGCCCAUCUGGUGGGUCAGGACCUGCAGGGGACCCGGAGGCUCCCACCCCCACCUCUCAGGACUCUGCCUCCACCACCCCCGUGGGCAUGCACUGAAGGGUUGCCUGCAGGGUCUCCAGGCGAGGGGGACCCCACAGGGUGGGCAGCGCCUUCUCCCGGCUUCCCCACAGUCCCCUGCAGCGUCCCGUCUGGCUGUUGACCUACAUGUGGUCGGGCACACCUCACACUACAAGGCUACCCCUGGGCCCAUCCCUGCCCCUUCCACGGCCCCCACCUGUGGUCAGGUGUUGCCACCCCCUCAGGACCUGGUCUCAAGGCAGCCCCACUCGAGUCUUCUGGAGUCCAAGGCACGCCACUCGCCCAAAAGGGAGGGGGUGUUUGGGGGGGCUUUGACUGUCUCCAGACCUCAGGGGAGCUGGGCAGGCUCUAACCAGUGGUCCUCCAGAGAGCAGCGUUGACCACCUGGACCCCUGCGCCACGUGACAGGAGGCUCUGGUCCUGCAGGCCUGGUCUUGCCCAGCUGGGCUGCCUCAGGUGUCAGGAAGGGGAUGGGUGUCCCUGGCUCCCAGGCCAGGCAGCUGCUGACCUCCAGCACCCCGCACUUGCUCAUGAGGACCCCACCCCCGCAGGCCCUCCCGGGUCCUGACCAGCCUCUGGUGCAGCAUCUGCUUUGGCCUCCGGGCCCCCUCGCUCCCCAC